GGCAGUUUCCCGACCAGAGAGAACGAACGUGUCUGCGGGCGCGCGGGGAGCAGAGGCGGUGGCGGGCGGCGGCGGCACCGGGAGCCGCCGAGUGACCCUCCCCCGCCCCUCUGGCCCCCCACCCUCCCACCCGCCCGUGGCCCGCGCCCAUGGCCGCGCGCGCUCCACACAACUCACCGGAGUCCGCGCCUUGCGCCGCCGACCAGUUCGCAGCUCCGCGCCACGGCAGCCAGUCUCACCUGGCGGCACCGCCCGCCCACCGCCCCGGCCACAGCCCCUGCGCCCACGGCAGCACUCGAGGCGACCGCGACAGUGGUGGGGGACGCUGCUGAGUGGAAGAGAGCGCAGCCCGGCCACCGGACCUACUUACUCGCCUUGCUGAUUGUCUAUUUUUGCGUUUACAACUUUUCUAAGAACUUUUGUAUACAAAGGAACUUUUUAAAAAAGACGCUUCCAAGUUAUAUUUAAUCCAAAGAAGAAGGAUCUCGGCCAAUUUGGGGUUUUGGGUUUUGGCUUCGUUUCUUCUCUUCGUUGACUUUGGGGUUCAGGUGCCCCAGCUGCUUCGGGCUGCCGAGGACCUUCUGGGCCCCCACAUUAAUGAGGCAGCCACCUGGCGAGUCUGACAUGGCUGUCAGCGACGCGCUGCUCCCAUCUUUCUCCACGUUCGCGUCUGGCCCGGCGGGAAGGGAGAAGACACUGCGUCAAGCAGGUGCCCCGAAUAACCGCUGGCGGGAGGAGCUCUCCCACAUGAAGCGACUUCCCCCAGUGCUUCCCGGCCGCCCCUAUGACCUGGCGGCGGCGACCGUGGCCACAGACCUGGAGAGCGGCGGAGCCGGUGCGGCUUGCGGCGGUAGCAACCUGGCGCCCCUACCUCGGAGAGAGACCGAGGAGUUCAACGAUCUCCUGGACCUGGACUUUAUUCUCUCCAAUUCGCUGACCCAUCCUCCGGAGUCAGUGGCCGCCACCGUGUCCUCGUCAGCGUCAGCCUCCUCUUCGUCGUCGCCGUCGAGCAGCGGCCCUGCCAGCGCGCCCUCCACCUGCAGCUUCACCUAUCCGAUCCGGGCCGGGAACGACCCGGGCGUGGCGCCGGGCGGCACGGGCGGAGGCCUCCUCUAUGGCAGGGAGUCCGCUCCCCCUCCGACGGCUCCCUUCAACCUGGCGGACAUCAACGACGUGAGCCCCUCGGGCGGCUUCGUGGCCGAGCUCCUGCGGCCAGAAUUGGACCCGGUGUACAUUCCGCCGCAGCAGCCGCAGCCGCCAGGUGGCGGGCUGAUGGGCAAGUUCGUGCUGAAGGCGUCGCUGAGCGCCCCUGGCAGCGAGUACGGCAGCCCGUCGGUCAUCAGCGUCAGCAAAGGCAGCCCUGACGGCAGCCACCCGGUGGUGGUGGCGCCCUACAACGGCGGGCCGCCGCGCACGUGCCCCAAGAUCAAGCAGGAGGCGGUCUCUUCGUGCACCCACUUGGGCGCUGGACCCCCUCUCAGCAAUGGCCACCGGCCGGCUGCACACGACUUCCCCCUGGGGCGGCAGCUCCCCAGCAGGACUACCCCGACCCUGGGUCUUGAGGAAGUGCUGAGCAGCAGGGACUGUCACCCUGCCCUGCCGCUUCCUCCCGGCUUCCAUCCCCACCCGGGGCCCAAUUACCCAUCCUUCCUGCCCGAUCAGAUGCAGCCGCAAGUCCCGCCGCUCCAUUACCAAGGUCAGUCCCGGGGAUUUGUAGCUCGGGCUGGGGAGCCCUGUGUGUGCUGGCCCCACUUCGGGACACACGGGAUGAUGCUCACCCCACCUUCUUCACCCCUAGAGCUCAUGCCACCCGGUUCCUGCAUGCCAGAGGAGCCCAAGCCAAAGAGGGGAAGACGAUCGUGGCCCCGGAAAAGGACCGCCACCCACACUUGUGAUUACGCGGGCUGCGGCAAAACCUACACAAAGAGUUCCCAUCUCAAGGCACACCUGCGAACCCACACAGGUGAGAAACCUUACCACUGUGACUGGGACGGCUGUGGAUGGAAAUUCGCCCGCUCAGAUGAACUGACCAGGCACUACCGUAAACACACGGGGCACCGCCCGUUCCAGUGCCAAAAAUGCGACCGAGCAUUUUCCAGGUCGGACCACCUCGCCUUACACAUGAAGAGGCAUUUUUAAAUCCCAGACAGUGGAUAUGACCCACACUGCCAGAAGAGAAUUCAGUAUUUUUUACUUUUCACACUGUCUUCCCGAUGAGGGAAGGAGCCCAGCCAGAAAGCACUACAAUCAUGGUCAAGUUCCCAACUGAGUCAUCUUGUGAGUGGAUAAUCAGGAAAAAUGAGGAAUCCAAAAGACAAAAAUCAAAGAACAGAUGGGGUCUGUGACUGGAUCUUCUAUCAUUCCAAUUCUAAAUCCGACUUGAAUAUUCCUGGACUUACAAAAUGCCAAGGGGGUGACUGGAAGUUGUGGAUAUCAGGGUAUAAAUUAUAUCCGUGAGUUGGGGGAGGGAAGACCAGAAUUCCCUUGAAUUGUGUAUUGAUGCAAUAUAAGCAUAAAAGAUCACCUUGUAUUCUCUUUACCUUCUAAAAGCCAUUAUUAUGAUGUUAGAAGAAGAGGAAGAAAUUCAGGUACAGAAAACAUGUUUAAAUAGCCUAAAUGAUGGUGCUUGGUGAGUCUUGGUUCUAAAGGUACCAAACAAGGAAGCCAAAGUUUUCAAACUGCUGCAUACUUUGACAAGGAAAAUCUAUAUUUGUCUUCCGAUCAACAUUUAUGACCUAAGUCAGGUAAUAUACCUGGUUUACUUCUUUAGCAUUUUUAUGCAGACAGUCUGUUAUGCACUGUGGUUUCAGAUGUGCAAUAAUUUGUACAAUGGUUUAUUCCCAAGUAUGCCUUAAGCAGAACAAAUGUGUUUUUCUAUAUAGUUCCUUGCCUUAAUAAAUAUGUAAUAUAAAUUUAAGCAAACGUCUAUUUUGUAUAUUUGUAAACUACAAAGUAAAAUGAACAUUUUGUGGAGUUUGUAUUUUGCAUACUCAAGGUGAGAAUUAAGUUUUAAAUAAACCUAUAAUAUUUUAUCUGAA